AGUGUUUGGGUUUCUUCGCGGCUGCUCAAGAUGAACCGACUCUUCGGGAAAGCGAAACCCAAGGCUCCGCCGCCCAGCCUGACUGACUGCAUUGGCACGGUGGACAGUAGAGCAGAAUCCAUUGACAAGAAGAUUUCUCGAUUGGAUGCUGAGCUAGUGAAGUAUAAGGAUCAGAUCAAGAAGAUGAGAGAGGGUCCUGCAAAGAAUAUGGUCAAGCAGAAAGCCUUGCGAGUUUUAAAGCAAAAGAGGAUGUAUGAGCAGCAGCGGGACAAUCUUGCCCAACAGUCAUUCAACAUGGAACAAGCCAAUUAUACCAUCCAGUCUUUGAAGGACACCAAGACCACGGUUGAUGCUAUGAAACUGGGAGUAAAGGAAAUGAAGAAGGCAUACAAGCAAGUGAAGAUCGACCAGAUUGAGGAUUUACAAGACCAGCUAGAGGAUAUGAUGGAAGAUGCAAAUGAAAUCCAAGAAGCACUGAGUCGCAGUUAUGGCACCCCAGAACUGGAUGAAGAUGAUUUAGAAGCAGAGUUGGAUGCACUAGGUGAUGAGCUUCUGGCUGAUGAAGACAGUUCUUAUUUGGAUGAGGCAGCAUCUGCACCUGCAAUUCCAGAAGGUGUUCCCACUGAUACAAAAAACAAGGAUGGAGUUCUGGUGGAUGAAUUUGGAUUGCCACAGAUCCCUGCUUCAUAGAUUUGCAUCAUUCAAGCAUAUCUUGUAAAACAAACACAUAUUAUGGGACUAGGAAAUAUUUAUCUUUCCAAAUUUGCCAUAACAGAUUUAGGUUUCUUUCCUUUCUUUGAAGGAAAGUUUAAUUACAUUGCUCUUUUAUUUUUUCCAUUAAGAGACUCAUUGCUUGGGAAAUGCUUUCUUCGUACUAAAAUUUGAUUCCUUUUUUUCUUAUGAAAAACGAACUCAGUUUAAAAGUAUUUUUAGCUCGUAUGACUUGUUUUCAUUCAUUAAUAAUAAUUUGAAAUAAAACUAAGGAAAUGGAAUCUUAAAAGUCUAUGACAGUGUAACUCUACAGUCUCAAAAUGACCUGAUAAAUUGAUAAGACAAAGAUGAGAUUAUUGGGGCUGUUCAUAUUAUGAUUCAGAAUCAUUUUCUAUUGUGGUAUUAUAGGUUGGUUAAAGUGAUGGCCUUUUUGAUGGGUUUUGUUGUGUCUUGUGAACAAGUCGUUACUGUGUCCAUUAUUGGAAUGGAAUUAUCACUACUGUAUCAUGAGUGGGUAUUUUGAUUCUAUGGUUCCCUCAGUAUUACAUCUUGACUUGUAAUCAAUUAUGAAUAUUUCUUGAUAUUUAAUGUAUAGGACAUUUAUUUAUACUCAAUAAAUAUUUUUCAAAAGGAUAUAAUUUUAAUAAUAUCACUUCAGCUUAAAACCUCUACUGCGGAAACCAAAUUUAAUAGAAUUUUAAUGUCAUUUCAGCCUAUAACUCCACUACAGAAACCAAAUUAACCAGUAGCAUUGUGAGGAAAGAGCAAGGAACAAUCUGGGCUUGGGCCCUGGGUCUACCAUUUACUAACUACUGAGUAGUCUAUUCAACCUCUCUAACCUUCUGUUUCCUUAUUAGUAAAAUCAUGCUUAACUCACAGAGCUUUUGUGAGGAAUAAUUGAGGUAAUGGUCAUAAGUACCUUGUUAACUGCAAGGGGCUAUUCUUAUAUGAGGGAUUGUUAACAAUAAAAAAGAAACUGCUUCAUUCUUUUCUUGGAAGGUGCCUGGAGUACUACAGCAAGUUCAAACUCCUGCCCAAUUUCAGGGUCUUUAAUGAUCCUGUCCUCCCUUCCUCAUUCAACUUGUUGCCAACAGCAUGGCCCCUCCAGCCUAGCUGGGUGCCUCACAGUGCUAUGUGCACCUGACUCUCAUGUGUCUGCAGAUCAAACCAAUAAACAUUUAGGAACACCA